AGCUCGCGUACUGCACGUGGACCUCUGCGCCGCCCCCACCGAGUGAGGCUCAGGCACCCGAAGCGUCUGGAGUUGUUUUGAGGCUGUCCUCGCGUUAUCUACUUCGCAGCAGGCAGGGGACCAGUGUCCCCGCACCUGUGACUGUUUUUUUUUUUUUAAACCCAGUGUUUAAGUUCAGGAAGAACUCAGGGCUCCCCUGGACUGGGUGUGCCUGGAUUUCAAGUUCUAUUCAGGGAGAGGAUCCCAGGCCUUAUAUUGGUCCUGAUUUCUUCAGAUUCCCUAUUAGCACGAUUUCUACGAGGCCCAACACAAACCCAGUUUACCAGACCUCCGAUUAUACAAGAAAUCUUGCAGAAGAAAGAAAAAGCAAUAGAAAGAAGACGUGAGGAGGAAACACAUCCGUCUGCACAUGGAAGGGGCGCUGACUGCCCGGGACAAGGUCGGGGUUCAGGAUUUUGUGCUAUUGGACGCGUACACCAGCGAAUCUGCCUUUGUCGACAACCUCCGCAAGCGUUUCAGCGAGAACCUCAUAUACACAUAUAUUGGCACCCUCCUUGUGUCUGUGAAUCCAUACCAGGAGCUCGGAAUCUACACUGUGAGCCAGAUGGAACUUUAUCAAGGGGUCAAUUUCUUUGAACUGCCACCACAUGUCUACGCUAUAGCCGACAACGCUUACCGAAUGAUGUGUGCUGAACUAAAUAACCAUUUCAUCCUCAUUUCUGGAGAGAGUGGGGCAGGGAAAACAGAGGCCUCCAAGAAAAUUCUCGAGUAUUUUGCAGUGACCUGCCCAAUGACCCAGUCACUACAAAUAGCCCGUGACAGACUGCUGUUCUCCAACCCAGUGCUGGAGGCUUUUGGAAAUGCCAGAACGCUCCGGAAUGACAACUCCAGCAGAUUUGGGAAAUACAUGGAUAUACAAUUUGAUUUUCAGGGCAUUCCCGUAGGUGGGCAUAUCAUCAGUUACUUGAUAGAGAAGUCCCGAGUUGUCUACCAAAACGAAGGCGAGCGGAAUUUCCACAUCUUCUACCAGCUGCUGGCAGGUGGCGAAGAGGAGCGCCUGUCUUACCUGGGACUCGAGCGAGACCCCCAGCUGUAUAAAUACCUCUCACAGGGUCAUUGUGCCAAAGAGUCAUCCAUUAGUGACAAGAAUGACUGGAAAACUGUUUCCAACGCCUUUUCUGUCAUUGAUUUUACUGAAGCUGACCUCGAGAAUCUCUUUGGAAUUAUUGCCAGUGUCUUACACCUGGGGAACAUUGGUUUUGAAGAAGACGACCAAGGCUGUGCCACUAUCCCAGACACCCAUGAGAUCAAGUGGAUAGCCAAGCUCCUGGGGGUCCACCCAUCAGUCCUUCUGGAAGCUCUCACCCACAGAAAAAUUGAAGCCAAAACUGAGGAGGUGAUCUGCCCGUUGACACUAGAACUCUCUGUCUACGCUAGAGAUGCAAUGGCAAAGGCUGUUUAUGGACGAACGUUUACUUGGCUGGUCAACAAAAUCAAUUCCUCCUUAGUUAACAAGGAUUUCACCAGGAAAACUGUAAUUGGAUUACUGGACAUCUAUGGGUUUGAAGUCUUUGACAAGAAUGGUUUUGAACAGUUCUGUAUAAAUUACUGCAAUGAGAAACUCCAGCAACUGUUAAUUGAGAGGACUCUAAAAGCAGAACAGGCAGAAUAUGAAAUGGAAGGCAUAGAGUGGGAGCCAAUUAAAUAUUUCAACAACAAGAUCAUCUGUGAUUUGGUAGAAGAGAGACAUAAAGGAAUCAUAUCUAUUCUGGAUGAAGAAUGCAUUCGGCCUGGUCCUGCUACAGACUUGAGUUUCCUGGAGAAAUUGGAAGAGAAAGUGGGCAAACAUGCACACUUCGAAACCCGUAAGCUGGCUGGUCCAAAGGGCCGAAAGAGGAUUGGCUGGAUGGAGUUCCGACUCCUCCACUAUGCAGGAGAGGUCACAUACUGCACCAAGGGAUUCUUGGAAAAAAACAAUGAUCUUCUUUACAGACAUCUGAAAGAAGUGCUGUGCAAGUCCAAGAACAUUAUCCUGAGGGAAUGCUUCCUGCUGGCCGAGUUAGAAAACCGGAGGAGGCCCCCAACAGUGGGGACUCAGUUUAAAAACAGUCUGAGCAGCCUUCUAGAAACCCUCAUCUCUAAGGAGCCCUCCUACAUCCGUUGCAUCAAGCCCAACGACAGGAAAGAACCCAGCAAAUUUGAUGACUUCCUCAUAAGGCAUCAGAUCAAAUACCUGGGGCUGAUGGAGCACCUGCGGGUGAGACGGGCUGGUUUUGCAUACCGAAGGAAAUACGAGCAUUUCUUGCAAAGAUACCUAGGAGUGGAAUUGAGUCACUGGGUUGAGCGUCUGAUGAUGUCAUUGUUCUACAAAGACAGGUACAAGUCCUUAUGCCCAGACACCUGGCCGCACUGGCACGGGCCUCCAGCAGAGGGCGUGGAACGGCUGAUCAAGUACAUCGGCUACAAACCCGAGGAAUACAAGUUAGGCAAAACCAAAAUAUUCAUUCGUUUCCCCAGAACUCUGUUUGCUACCGAAGAUGCCUUUGAAUUUAGUAAACAUCAACUAGUUGCAAGAAUCCAAGCCACUUACAAACGCUGCCUAGGAAGGAGAGAAUACGUGAAAAAAAGACAAGCAGCCAUCAAACUGGAAGCCCACUGGCGUGGGGCCCUGGCUCGGAAGGCAAUCCAAAGGAGAAAGUGGGCCGUGCGGAUUAUCAGAAAGUUCAUUAAAGGAUUCAUCAGUCGCAACAAACCCCUCUGUCCUGACAACGAGGAAUUUAUCGUGUUUGUGCGGAAGAAUUACAUCUUGAAUCUCCGGUAUCACCUUCCAAAGACUGUCCUGGACAAGAGCUGGCUGAGGCCUCCUGGCAUCUUGGAAAAUGCAUCAGAUCUGCUCAGGAAAAUGUGCGUGAGGAACCUGGUGCAGAAGUACUGCCGCGGGAUCACAGCUGAGCGGAAAGCAAUGAUGCAGCAAAAGGUAGUUACAAGUGAAAUCUUCAGGGGAAGGAAAGACGGCUACACAGAAAGUUUAAAUCAACCCUUUGUCAACAGUCGGAUAGAUGAAGGAGACAUUAAUCCGAAAGUGCUUCAGCUAAUUAGCCAUGAGAAAAUCCAGUAUGGUGUCCCGGUCAUUAAAUAUGACAGAAAAGGCUUCAAAGCACGGCAGCGGCAACUCAUUCUUACUCAGAAAGCAGCUUACGUGGUGGAACUUGCCAAAAUCAAGCAGAAAAUAGAGUACUCAGCUCUCAAAGGUGUCUCCACUAGCAAUCUGAGUGAUGGAAUCUUAGUCAUUCAUGUUUCACCAGAGGACAGCAAGCAAAAGGGGGAUGCCGUUUUGCAGUGUGGACACGUGUUUGAAGCAGUUACUAAACUCGUCAUGCUGGUUAAGAAGGAGAACAUUGUCAAUGUUGUUCAAGGAAGUUUACAGUUUUUUAUUAGUCCGGGAAAAGAAGGCACAAUAGUUUUCGACACUGGACUGGAAGAACAAGUCUAUAAAAAUAAAAAUGGACAAUUAACAGUGGUGUCAGUCCGGAGGAAGUCCUGAUAGAGGAUGACGUCUGACCUCUACCAUCGCCAUUUUUGCUCCAACUGAGGAAACUACAGGGGAAGUGGGGAUUGGAUCCAGUUAGCUACCUCUUCAAGGUACCAGGCCCGCAGCACUAACAGAUCACAUCUGAAGAAACUGAGGGGCGUUAGGCCAAAGCCUAAUCCCAGCUCCUCAGCUGCCCCAUGGCACCUUAUUUAAAAUGUCACCUUCUGGAAGCAGACCCCAGGUCACCCGAAGGCGCAAUUCUAAACACCCUCGACAGGAUCUAUGUUCAGUGCGCAGUCCAACGUGUCAUUAGAGGGUGGGCAAGAUUCUCUACCUCUGUCAAGCUGCCCUGAGACAUGAUGAAAUACUGUGUACAGCAAGUUCUCAAAUAACAUUUCGUUAUAUGUUGAUAAGACAUCUGAUUCCUGGGCAGGGCCACUGUCUGGGUGGAGUCUGUAUGUUCUCCCCAUGUCUCUGGGUUUCUUCUGGGUGCUCUGGUUUCCUCCCACGUCCCCAAGGUGUGUGUGUCAGGUGCACUGGCGUGUCUAUGCGGUCCCAGUCUGAGUGAGUGUGGGUGCGUGAGCCCCGUGAGAGGAGGACAUCCUGUCCAGGGUGGGUCCCGCCUUCUGCCCUGAGCUGCUGGGAUUGGGCUCUGGCCAUCUGCAACCCUGAACGUGCAGGUUGGAGAACGAAUGAAUACAAAUUUUAUUGUAAAAUAAAAAUGUAUAUAAAGCAUAUGAGCACACAAAUGGACAAUAAAUGCCACAGCGCAAAAGCGUGUAGCGAGCCUGCCACGCUUGUGACUGGGGAGGGGCUCCGUAUAAUCUCACCUUUGCAAGCGUUUAUUUACUGAUGUAUGCGGCCACCACUGUGACCACCAUCACUUACCGAUUCACCAAAACUUAGGUAAUAUGGUCUUAUUUUUGAUUUAAUUAAAUAUACGUGUAGCUCAUGUAUUUCACAGUUUAAUAUGAGAAGUGCUUUGGUCUUUAUUUAGAAAUUGGGUGAUGUUUUUGUGCCCAGCAACAUGCUGUAGGAAUUUAACUCUUGUUUACAUCCAUUAGCCUCAUGGUUUUGCUUCAAGUCUCAGCUUCCAAGAACCUAUCGAUGACUUACUGUGCAUGGUCUGAGACUAAGUAAAGGAAAUUUCCUAAAGCUGUGAAAUUUGAAUUUUGCUUUAAAUAAAUGGAACUCACAUGUGUCAAGGGA